GCUGUCGCCGCCGCGGAGACAAAGAUGGCUGCGAGAGUCGGCGCCUUCCUCAAGAAUGCCUGGGACAAGGAGCCAGUGCUGGUCGUGUCCUUCGUCGUCGGGGGCCUCGCUGUAAUUCUGCCCCCAUUGAGCCCCUACUUCAAGUACUCCGUCAUGAUCAACAAGGCCACGCCCUACAACUACCCAGUGCCCGUCCGUGAUGAUGGGAACAUGCCCGACGUGCCCAGCCACCCCCAGGACCCUCAGGGCCCCAGCCUGGAGUGGCUGAAGAAACUGUGAGCACCUCCACUGACAGAGGCGGCCCCUCCCACGGCUCCCAAUAAAAAUGUGAAAACCAACCCCCGAACGUGAGCAUGUGUGUGAUCAGAGGUGGGAACAAGUAGACGGUGGCCGGGGUGAGUGUGGGGUCAGUUUAUUGGGCAUGCGUCAGUCAGAGGCUGGGCUGGCCAGGGUCGGGUAGGGCAGCAGUUUGUCUGGACCCCGAGAAACCCAACUGGAAUCCAGGGCCUCAUCUGCUUCAAAGCCAAAGUCUUCCUCAACCUUAAUCUGCAGGAGAUAAGGAACAAGGUGUUAACAGGCCUGGGAAUCUAGAAAAUCCCAUCAGCUUCACCAUUUUUGUUUUCAUUUUGUUUUGCUUUUUAAAGAGACAGGGUCUCACUCUGUUGCCCAGGCUGGAGUGCAGUGGUGCCAUCAUAGUUCACUGCAGCCUCUGCCUCCCAGGCUCAAGUGAUCCUCCCACCUCAGCUUCCCAAGUAGCUGGGACUACAGGCACUUGCCAACCAAGCCUAACAUGUUUUUUCUUUUUGGUAGAGAUGGGGUCUCAGUAUGUUGCUCAGGCAGGUCUCAGACUCCUGGCCUCAAGUGAUCCUCCCACCUAGGCCUCCCAAAGUGCCGGGAUUACAGGCAUGAGCCACUGCACCUGGCCAGCCUCACAGUUCUUGUCUG